AAAAGGGGCUGAAAUCCUGGGGACCUCAGAGUCGUCUAAAACUCCUAGCCAUGUUCCAGCAGUUCCAGGCCUCCUGUCUUGUCCUGUUUUUCCUGGUUGGCUUUGCUCAGCAGACCCUAAAGCCUCAAAAUAGGAAGGUGGAUUGCAACAAAGGGGUAACAGGCACCAUCUAUGAGUAUGGAGCCCUCACCCUCAACGGCGAGGAGUACAUCCAAUUCAAGCAGUUUGCAGGCAAGCACGUCCUGUUUGUCAAUGUGGCCGCCUAUUGAGGCUUGGCAGCUCAGUAUCCUGAACUGAAUGCACUACAGGAGGAGCUGAAGAAUUUUGGUGUCAUUGUGUUGGCCUUUCCCUGCAACCAGUUUGGAAAACAAGAACCAGGAACAAACUCAGAAAUACUUCUUGGUCUCAAGUAUGUGUGUCCAGGUAGUGGCUUUGUCCCCAGUUUCCAGCUCUUUGAGAAAGGGGAUGUGAAUGGAGAAAAAGAACAGAAGGUCUUUACUUUCCUGAAGAACUCCUGCCCUCCGACCUCUGAUCUUUUGGGCUCAUCAAGCCAACUCUUCUGGGAGCCCAUGAAGGUCCAUGAUAUCCGCUGGAACUUUGAGAAAUUUCUGGUGGGGCCCGAUGGAGUCCCUGUCAUGCAUUGGUUCCACCAGGCUCCAGUCAGCACAGUCAAGUCAGACAUCCUGGAGUACCUAAAGCAGUUCAAUACCCACUAGGAAGGGCUAGCGACUGACAGAAAUAACUACCCUGUCUCCCACCUGCAGGAAUGUCUAACAAAGCAUCCAUCUUCCUCCUUCUUUGCUCCACACUCGUGCCUACCCAGCCUCCUGAUGACCAAACCAUCCUGUACUACCCAAGCACCUGCUUAGCAUGUGUGUGUAGCUGUGUGUGUGUGUGUGUGUGUGUGUAUGGAUAUGUAGAAUUGUAUUUGUUGGUAUAUGCAUAGGUGUAUGUAUGGUGUGUGUGUGUGUGUGUGUGUGUGUGUUUGAAGAUUAAGGAAAAGAACACCUAUCUCUCCAACUCUCUGAUCCUGAAAUAUCUAUUCCAAAGGAAAAUCAUAUUUUAGGGUAGAUGAAUCAGACUAUCCUGUGUCCCUAAAAAAGCAAUCCCGAGAAGUUGUGACAUCUAUCCCUUCCCCUUCCUGAAAGUUUUAAAGAAAGCAGGAGCUGGCCGCAAGACUCUAGGCCUCCUUCAUAGCCUCUCUCCUCUAAGAUAGGCAUGCAUUGUUAAACUCUUUUCUCCUUAAUUCUCCUUUAUUCCCCUGCCACCCAGUAGUUCUCAUGUAGGACCUCUGAAGGCAGAGUGAGAGCAGAAACCCCACCUCACAUGAAGGGAAGGGCAUCUCCAUGAUGGUGGAUCCCAAAACCCCUCUGGGUCGCACCCUGCCAGAGCCUUCCUUGGUGCCUGUCCCUUAGUGCAUUCAGGUCAUGGCACCUGGGCAGGGGUGUCCCUGUAUUCUGAAUGAUGGGCUUUCUCCUCACCCUGAGCCUCCUCAACUUUAAGCUUAUUUUGAUCACUGUCUCAAAUUUAAAAAUUCUGCAGCAACCUGGCUCUGUGUGGUGUUUUCCCAGUCCCAUAUUAUGUCCAGUCAUACUUCUUCUUUCUCUGUCACUUUGUCCCUGCUUUCUUGAUUCCCUUGUCUUGUUCUUCAGUAUUUUGUUUUUCUCAAAAAUGCUCUAGAACUUUCCUUGGCACAUAUAAAAGCACGGCUG